AGAGAUUGGGGGACAGAAGGAAGUGCAUUAAUUCCUUCCACGACCCCUGAAGAGCAGCGGUGGGUCUGAGCAUCCUAUCUCCAGGAAGCAGGCCAGCAGGCAAGCCAGCUGCCACCUCGUCCUGUGCAAAGCACAGGCACCGUCCCCAAAAGAUUUCCAAAGAUGAUGUUAAACCCAGCCACGGUUCUGAUCUCCAGGAAAGCAAUUGCUGUGGUACAAAAGGACAAGGGUUAAAAGAGAACAGUGGGAGCUCUCUUUCCCAGCUAACUCACGCAGUGUGACGCAGAGGCUUUCAGCACAGCCCAGGGUGCCCGGGACUGAAAACUCCUUCACCAGCCCCCUCCACAGGUGGGAAAUACUCGGAUCUUCAUUCUUGUGACACAAGACCUUGAAAGUUGCUGAAAAAUGCUAGUCCCGUCUGACUGGGGCAGCAUUUUCAUUUAUUGCACACCAUUGGGUUUUUUUGUUUGUUUGUUUUUGUGGCUUUAUUUGUUUAUUUUUUUUGAGAUGGAGUUUUACUCUGUUGGCCAGCCUGGAGUGCAGUGGCACAAUCUUUGCUCACUGCAACCUCUGCCUCCCAGGUUCAAGCAAUUCUCCUGCCUCAGCCUCCCGAGUAGCUGGGAUUACAGGUGCGUGCCACCACGCCCGGCUAAUUUUUGUAUUUUUUUAGUAGAGACAGAGUGUCACCAUGUUGGCCAGGCUAGUCUUGAACUCCUGACCUCAAGUGACCCACCCACCUCGGCCUCCCAAAGUGCUGGGAUUACAAGCUUGAGCCACUAUGCCCAACCACCAUUAAGAUUUUGGCAGGAAUCAUUGUGCUAGACACCACUAUCCCACCAAUCACUGAGCACUUUUCAUUUCCUGCCGCUGGUGCUGUUGGAUACCUUACGGCAAGCUGCCGUCCCUGCCCACCCACCUGAGGACAGGAACCUCCAACUCUGCCUUGCCAGAACUGACCAGUGUGUCUGACAGAUGGAUAUAGAAGACUUAGAUCACUACGAGAUGAAAGCAGAGCCCAUUAGUGGGAAAAAGUUGGAGGAUGAAGGAAUUGAAAAAGAAAAUUUGGCAAUAUUAGAGAAAUUAGGAAGACUGAAAGACAAGAGCAUUUAACUGCAAACUGUUGUCGUUGUCAACUGGGUUGUCUUCCUGAAGUAUGAAUCCGGUAUGUAUUGUGUGGAGGAGCAUUACGUAUUGAACUUCUCACAAAACAGGGCUGAAGCAGUGCCUACUCGACAGAACCGGUCAUCGUACAAAGAAAUGCCACGUGACUCAAAGGCAAAGCCAGAGUGCAGCUUGGAGCAAAGAAGAUGAUGUCUCACUCUGUCACCCAAGAUGGAGUGCAAUGGCACGAUCUCAGCUCACUGCAACCUCUGCCUCCCAGGUUCAAGCAAUUAUCCUGCCUCAGCCACCCGAGUAGCUGAGAUUACAGGCCUCUGCCACCAUGCUCAGCUAUUUUUUGUAUUUUUAGUAGAGACGGGGUUUCACCAUGUUGGGCAGGCUAGUCUUGGAACUACUGACCUCAGGUGAUCCGCCCACUUUGGCCUCCCGAAAGUGCUGGGAUUACAGUCAUGAGCCACCAUGCCCAGCCUAUUUAUUUCUGAUUCUUUAAGGGUGAGUAGAAAUUUUUUCCAGGUGACUAAAACCUUGAGACAUUAUUCCAAGCAGAGACCAGCGGGGCAGAGACACGGGGAUAUAGAGAUGUUGAAGUUUACCAAACACUGCUAGAUUUAAAAAACAGAAAAGAAACAAUCAAAAUCAAAAAUUAAAAUUAAAAAUCACCUAAAAAAAAAGAAACUGUUAAUGGGCUUGUCCAAAGGUGACGUCACAAUUGAGUUAACUAUGACCAUAGACACACAAUAAUGGAUGGAAGUUUUGGGGAAAAAACAUAACAUUCUCAGGUUGUUGGCAGAGUAUCUAGAACAAUUUAGAAAUACAGAUAUUGAAUUCUGGGAAUAAUUACACUGUAGUGAAAUCAUUUCCUUCUCUGCGUAUGAAGCAUGUAUGUGUGGCACACUGUUCAAGGUGCUGAAAAUCAGACUCUUCUCAAGGAGCUCAUGAGCAAUCAAGGGAGAUGGAUGGGUGAGCCACUGAUUAUCAUGUGACAAGUGGGGUAAUAGAGAUAUGACUAAAAUGCUAUCCAAAGAAGAAGAAAGGAAUUAUUCAUAGUAUAUGGAGUGCUGGGGAAAGAGUUCUGAAAUGAAGCCGGCCGGGUGUGAUGGCUCACACUUCCACUACCUGACCUCAGGUGAUCCACCAGACUCGGGCUCCCCAAAGUGCUGGGAUUACAGGUGUGAGCCACCGCACCCAGCCCAAAAGCUUUGUGUUUUUACGGAUAUUAACCAUGUUUCCUGUUUAAAAAGAAAAAACAGCAACAAUGUAGGAGAAUAAGAGAAACAUUUUUCCAAAAAAGAAAUCAUUUUGAUUAUUUUAUCUCAUUGGAAUGUUGGAUAAUAUAGUCUGCUUCAUUAAUCAUCAAGCAUGCUGUGGAUUUCCCACUUUUAUAGGAUCUGUAUCUCAGUUCAGGUAAUACUGGUAAUUUUUAUACAGUAUUUGAAGAUGAAAAAUAUAGGCCAAAAUGACAGACCUUGCAUAGAAGCUGGUUAAUGAAGACAGCUCUGGAGGAACACAUGGAUACACACAGAGAGACACACACAUAUAUAUAAAGUAUACACACAUAUGAUUUUUAAAGUUUUAAGGGUUUUAAAGCAAAAGCCAGCCCCUCCACUCUCCCAGAGCGGGCGGCCCCUCCCCUCUCUCAGAGUGGGUGGGGACAGCGGUUGCAUGGGCAGCUUUCCUGAUGAGCCACAGGUCCCUCUGGACACACUGCCGCCUGGCCACGCCCCCUUUCCCUGUCAUCUUUCUCGUUGGCCAAUGGGCUUGAAGCAUUAAGGCCACGCCCCUAUUCUGCAUUCUACUGUGGCCCUGGUUACGCUGCCUCUGGGUCAGUUACGCAGCUGUCUUCCAGGUGACUGGAUGUGUUGAUCAGCGCUCGCUGGGAUUUGGCUGACGUGGCCCCAGCCCCGCCUCCCUCCCCACCCCACAAUGGCAGAAGAAACUGGACAGAGUAAAUUAGCUGCAGCCAAGAAAAAGUUCAAAGAAUAUUGGCAGAGAAACCGCCCUGGUGUUCCAGCAGCAGCGAAGAGGAACACGAAAGCAAAUGGCAGUAGCCCUGAGACGGCCGCUUCUGGUGGUUGCCACUCAUCUGAGGCUGUGAGUCUUGCCUGGACAGGCUUUUGGGGACAGGGGGCCCAAGGAGCAGUAGAGGGCAAUCGUUAAGAUUGUGGAUGGACUGUUGGGUACUGGUGAAGGAUUCUGGAUUUGGCCGGGCACAGUGGCUCACGCCUGUAAUCCCCACACUUCGGGAGACCGAGGCAGGUGGAUCACAAGGUCAGGAGAUCGAGACCAUCCAGGCAAACACGGUGAAAUACUAAAAAAUACAAAAAAAAAAGCCGGGCGUGGUGGCGGGCGCCUGCAGUCCCAGCUGCUCCGGAGUCUGAGGGAGGAGAAUGGCGUGAACCUAGGAGGCGGAGCUUGCAGUGAGCCAAGAUCACGCCACUGCACUCCAGCCUGGAAGGCAGAGAGAGACUCCGUUUCAAAAAAGAAAAGAAUUCUGGGUUUGAAUCCUGCCUCUCCGUCUGCUAGGGAUAUGAUUUAGGGCAAGUUGCUUGAGCUCUUUGGGCCUCUGUUUUCACGUCUGUAUGAUAGAGGUGGUAUUGUUUGACUUGUAUUUGUGAAGUUUCAAUGAGAUUGAUAAUUGUCGAUUUUAUGUUAAUCCCUAGUACAUGGCCUGCUGUCAACACCCAGGACACCCAGGAUAUGGUCUUUGCUGUUUGAUUUUCCUCAUCCCCAGUCUCAAGGGGAAGCCAGGACAAUGAGAACAGCCACUUCCCAUCAGGAGUCACUGCAAGGCCCCCAGGGUGGGAUGGUGGGGAGAUAAGAACCGUGAGAGAAGUUGGCACAAAGGAGUUAUGGGACAAAGGGUCCAAGAUAGGCAGAAAAGAAAAUGUUGCCAGUUGAUGGGGAAGAAAGGAAGUCGGAGGGCUCAGACACUGAGGGGGACAGAACAUCUCCAUGUGCAGUCUCAUCUCUUAUAGUCAGCAACAGGUAUCCACGGGGAGGGCCCUACAUCAUCUGCUACCCUGAAGGAUCUGGAGGUAGGAGGCUCUGGGCGGAGGUGCAGUGACCCCGCAGGCCAGCCCUCCAACCUCCUCCCGCAGCGGGGACUGGGUGCCCCUCUGCCAGCUGAGACAGCCCACACACAACCCAGCCCUAAUGAUCGUUCUCUCUACCUCUCCCCCAAGUCCUCCUCCGCCUCCUCCUCUCUGCAUGCGCGUCAGAGCCCGUGCCAAGAACAAGCAGCAGUCCUGAACUCGAGGUCCAUAAAAAUCAGUCGACUGAAUGACACCAUCAAAUCUUUGAAACAACAGAAGAAACAAGUGGAACAUCAGCUGGAAGAAGAAAAGAAAGCAAACAAUGAGAAACAGAAAGCUGAAAGGGAGCUAGAGGGUCAAAUCCAGAGAUUGAACACAGAGAAAAAGAAACUAAAUACGGACCUGUAUCACAUGAAACAUUCUCUCAGAUACUUUGAAGAAGAGUCCAAGGAUCUGGCCGGCCGCCUGCAACGUUCAUCGCAGCGUAUAGGAGAGUUAGAGUGGUCUCUCUGUGCUGUCGCCGCCACACAGAAGAAGAAGCCGGAUGGGUUCUCGAGCCGCAGUAAAGCACUUCUCAAGCGGCAGUUAGAGCAGUCCAUACGGGAGCAGAUACUGCUGAAAGGACACGUGACACAGUUGAAGGAGUCGCUUAAAGAAGUCCAGCUGGAGAGAGAUCAAUAUGCUGAACAAAUAAAAGGAGAGAGGGCCCAGUGGCAGCAGAGGAUGAGGAAAAUGUCGCAGGAGGUUUGCACAUUGAAGGAGGAGAAGAAGCAUGAUACGCAUCGGGUAGAGGAGCUGGAGAGGAGCUUGUCCAGACUCAAAAACCAGAUGGCUGAGCCACUGCCCCCGGAUGCCCCAGCAGUGUCCUCUGAGGUGGAGCUGCAAGACCUGAGGAAGGAGCUGGAGAGAGUGGCAGGAGAGCUCCAGGCUCAGGUGGAAAACAAUCAGUGCAUCAGUCUCCUGAACCGUGGGCAAAAGGAGAGGCUUCGCGAGCAGGAGGAGAGGCUUCAGGAGCAGCAGGAGAGGCUUCGGGAACGGGAGAAGAGGCUUCAGCAGCUGGCCGAGCCACAGAGCGACUUGGAGGAGCUGAAGCACGAGAACAAGAGCGCACUGCAGUUGGAGCAGCAAGUAAAGGAGCUGCAGGAGAAGCUGGGCCAGGUGAUGGAGACGCUCACCUCGGCCGAGAAGGAGCCAGAGGCAGCAGUCCCAGCCUCAGGGACUGGGGGCGAGUCUAGCGGCCUUAUGGACCUCCUGGAGGAGAAGGCGGACCUGAGGGAGCAUGUGGAGAAACUGGAACUUGGAUUCAUCCAGUACCGGAGAGAGAGAUGCCAUCAGAAAGUACAUCGCCUUCUAACAGAGCCAGGGGACAGUGCCAAAGAUGCGUCACCGGGAGGAGGCCAUCAUCAGGCUGGCCCAGGACAAGGAGGAGAGGAAGGUGAAGCUGCUGGAGCUGCAGGAGAUGGUGUUGCGGCUUGUGGCAGCUACAGCGAGGGGCACGGCAAAUUCCUGGCCGCUGCCCGGAACCCUGCUGCUGAACCCAGUCCAGGAGCCCCAGCCCCCCAGGAGCUCGGGGCUGCCGACAAGCAUGGUGAUCUUUGUGAGGCGAGCCUCACCAACAGCGUGGAGCCUGCACAAGGAGAAGCCAGGGAGGGUUCUUCCCAGGACAACCCUACUGCACAGCCAGUCGUGCAGCUCCUUGGUGAGAUGCAGGACCACCAGGAGCACCCAGGCUUGGGCAGCAACUGCUGUGUGCCAUGCUUUUGCUGGGCUUGGCUGCCGAGAAGAAGGAGAUAAACACCACCAUCAUCAAAGAGCUGCUCAAGAAAUUUUUAAAAACGAAACAAAGUUAUGGGGUUAAUCUCCUACACAAUUCAUUUACUUCAUUUGAAUGUUAGAGCUACUCAUGAUUAUUUGUGUUUCUAAUUUAUAGUUUAAGUUUAUUUGUAAAAAGUUAAAAGAGAGUGGGUCUCUGUGGCUCUCACUGAUGUUCACUCUGGCAUCCUUCAGCAUUUUUCUUUUUUCAUUUCAUAAUUGUAGGUCAUUAGCAUGCAUAUCGAGUUUGCCCUUACGUGGUGGGAGUUCAAACACACAAAGACCCACUCUUUGCACAAAACUGUUCUCGCUGGUUUGGAAUAGGCUCCCGUGCUUUUCUAAUGUUAUUGCAGCAUGGAUGUCCAUUACAGAAUUCAGAUAAAAUUUGCUAAUGUUCUGCUAUGAUGUUUGAUCUCAUCUUAAUCACAGUGAGCUCUUCUAUAGCUCAAUAUGCGGUUUGCCCUCAAGUGUGCACUGUUUAUUACUUUGUAAUAUGCCACUGUGAGUACUGACAUUUAGAGCUGUUUAAAGGCCGAGAACUGGAAACAGCCUUUCCUCCAUUUUCUGUGUAUUGGUGAUGGGAGUGAUAACCUUUUGGGGGAGCUUUCUAAAUCUCACAGAAGAGGAAAGUGGCCUGCUCUGGCAGGUAUGUGCAGGAUACAGUGUGUUUCAUCUGUUCCGGUGCCAAGAAUGAGCAGUGUACUGUGGCAGUUCCCUUUGGAUUUGUAUGUGCUCUGGGCUCAUGAAGAUAUUGCAUCGUGAGCUGCAGCAGUUGCACUCUUUUUCAGUGACCUAAAAAGGGCUUAUUUCCGAGGAAUGAAAGGCUGCCAUCAUUGGCUGUGGGUGUGAAAAACCUUUCCUAGCUUAGAGCAUUUGUAUCUACAAUACAUUUUAAAGUCAGAGUUCGUGUUCCCUGUUUUAAUCACAUGACUACCUGUCCCAGUACACGAAAGGGCGCUGGUUGGCAUUCUUCUUAAUGUAUUUAGUGAAGAUCAUAAGAAAUCCUUUAAGAGUUUAAAUGUCUCUGAAACAGGCAUACAGGCUCUAGUCAAGAAUGAAUUAGAGUGAAGGAAAGCUGUGUGACACCUGGCAUUCCUCUCUGUUCAUGGAGCUUCUUUGAGGCUUGAAGUUUGAUUUUACUAUCUAGACCUCUCUGGCUAAUACCUAUUCUUCAACCACCUCGGUUACUCUGACAUAGGAAUUUACUUCUUUUCCUUGAGUGGAAAACACUUUAGAAAGUAAUAACAAACAUUAUUAUAAACUAAUAUAUGUGAGAGUACUUAGUUGAAACAAAAAGGAAUUUUAGUAGACAGUAUUAUAUUAUCUUUGAAAAUCAAGGAGAAGUUUAUGCAACUUAAAAUGUUUACACACUGUGGUGCAAUCUACUGUUUGUGAAUGUCUGUAUUAUCAGGAAACAUGUCUAUACGAUCGCAGAGUUGUAUUUCCUCACAAACUUCUUUACGAAGAGUGAAAUACGUUUUUGUACCUCUCAUUUUCAGUCAGGGACAUACUUUGUGCAAUAUUUCUGUGAUUGUGCCUAUGCAUGAUGAAUGAAUGCAUUUCAAUCAUACAUUGCCUAAAUCAUAACUUGAUGAUGCUUGGGAAAGAAUCAACAGUUAAAACUUCAUGAAGUUCUAAUGUCUGUGUUCCAAAACACAUCACAUUAUUAGGUUGUAGGGAGAUAUGUAGGUGUGCUCCCUGGGGUGGGGAGUUUUCUAGUUACUAGACCAUCUCCAUUUUUAGCACUUGGCAGCCUCAUGAUCCUUUUAUAAAUGUGAGAUUAACAGGAGAGCAGCAAUACGAUUUUGCCAAUGGAAUAACAGAUUUGCCGGCAUUCACUGAAAGAGGGCAGAUAUUGGGUCCUUGUAACUUCAACUGACUCUUCCAAAUUGUAUGAAUUUAUCAAUGUAUUACACAAAUCCAGUUUCAGAAUGAUAAAAAAUGUUAGACCAAAUAAUGCGGCUAAUUAACAGUCGUAUGAUUUCUAGCCCAUGGGUUUAAAACUGUAUCUUAAAGAGUCAUUUUAAAAUAAUAUAAAUAUUAAAAAAUGUAACUGCUAUCUUAAUGUUCUGAAAUAAAACAUUUUAAAAUAUAAAUCCUGUAGUUUAAAAGGAAGAAAUGGUGGGAAGGAAAAGUAGAGAAAGAAAUGCCAAUUCCAGGCCAAAGCGUUAUUUGCCAAGUUUUCUUAGAAUGAAUUUUACCAAUGUAUGAGUUCUUGUUAACAGAAUGUGUAACGGAAAUACUGAAAGACUUUUGCUUAAAGUGGCAUUAUUGACUGCUGAUGUGAUGCUACUGUAAUGCAAUAAAUUUUUAAAUUGUUGCAAA